UACCACUGCACUCCAGCCUGGGUGACAGAGCAAGAAUCCACCUCAAAAGAAAAAAUAACCUCAGAUGCAAGUGGCUCCACUCCAGCACAAUGCCCUUUGGAAUUCCAUGCUGCCUGGCCAAUGAGGAGAGCAAUAGAAAGCAAUCAAUAACAAGUUUCUAAAUUGUGUAACACAGAUAAUGUGGUUGCAGGUUAGUUGGAGGAGGCAGAGAUAAUUGGAGAUGAAAGGGUCUGGGAAGGCUUUGAAGGGAGAUAGAAUUUGAACUGGACCUUGAAGGACAUAGUGGAUUUUCUUCGACGGCUUGUGGAGAGUGAUCCCCAGGGCCUGCACCGGAUCCAUGUGGAUGGGAGCAGCGGGCGGCUGCAGCUGUGGCACCAUGAUUACCUCCUGGGCCACUUGGAUGAUGAAGGGAAAUCAACUGGACAGAGUGACAGGGGCAAGGGGGCUGAGGGACUGGGCACCUACUGUGGUCUCCGCAAGUCCUUCCUGUAUCCUCCCCAAGAGUCUGAGCCCUGCCCUCAAAGCCCCUCUGCCUCUGCCACCUUCCCCAGUGUCUCAGACAGCCUGCUUCAGGUGGCCAUGCCCCAGAAGCUCCUGGUGACAGAAGAGGAAGCCAAUCGCCUGGCUGAGGAGCUGGUGGCUGAGGAGGAGCGCAUGAAACAGAAAGCAGAGAAAAAGCGACUCAAGAAGAAGCGUCAAAAGGAACGGAAGCGACAGGAGCGUUUGGAGCAGUACUGUGGGGAGCCCAAGGCCAGCACUACCUCAGAUGGAGAUGAGAGCCCCCCAUCCAGCCCUGGAAACCCAGUUCAGGGACAGUGUGGUGAAGAAGAGGACUCACUGGAUCUAUCUAGCACUUUUGUGUCUCUGGCUUUGCGCAAGGUUGGGGAUUGGCCCCUCAGUGCCCGCAGAGAGAAGGGACUGAACCAGGAGCCCCAAGGCAGGGGUCUGGCCCUCCAGAAGAUGGGUCAAGAGGAAGAGAGCCCUCCAAGAGAGGAGAGGCCCCAGCAGAGUCCAAAGGUACAGGAGAAGGAUUUGGGGAGGCUGAGACCUCAAGACCUGCUUGACUUUGCACCCUAUCCCCAGGCAUCUCCGGGACUGCUGGCAGCUGCCUUACAACAGAGCCAGGAACUGGCAAAGUUGGGUACCAGCUUUGCUCAAAAUGGUUUCUACCAUGAGGCCGUGGUCCUCUUCACCCAGGCCUUGAAGCUCAACCCCCAGGACCACCGGUUAUUUGGAAAUCGUUCCUUCUGCCAUGAGCGGUUGGGUCAGCCAGCGUGGGCCCUGGCUGAUGCCCAGGUGGCCCUUACCCUACGGCCUGGCUGGCCCCGGGGCCUCUUCCGCCUGGGCAAGGCCUUGAUGGGACUACAGCGCUUCAGAGAGGCAGCUGCUGUGUUUCAGGAAACUCUGAGAGGUGGGUCCCAGCCUGACGCAGCCCGAGAGCUCCGCUCUUGCCUUCUCCACCUCACACUGCAGGGUCAGCGAGGAGGAAUCUGUGCACCACCUCUGUCACCUGGGGCCCUCCAGCCACUUCCCCAUGCUGAGCUGGCACCCUCAGGCCUACCUUCCCUCAGGUGCCCUCGAAGCACUGCUUUGAGGUCCCCUGGCCUGUCUCCACUCUUGCAUUAUCCUUCAUGUCACCGAAGCCACCCCAACCAGCCCCUCUCCCAGACUCAGAGUAGAAGGCCCCAUCCUCUCAAGCCCCAGGACCCUUCAAAGGGCUGGGACAUCCUGGGACUUGGGCUCCAGCAUCUGUCUCAGGCCAGAUGAGGGGGCACCGGUCCCUCAUAGGGCAGGGCCAUGUAUAUAUCCCUUGGUGGGGGACAUAGUGUGGUGACAGUUCACUGCAUAUUUUGAGACCUUAUUCUCUAGAUCCAUAGUUAAUGAUGCCCUGGCAGUCAUUCCUCUUGCCAUGGGGAAGCUUCUGAUGAGAGAAAGGAGCCCCACAUCCACUGAAACAUCCUUUGGUUCUCAAGCUUCUUCUGGAGGCAGUAAGGAAAAAUAAAACCCACCAAGGCUCAAGAAGGGAACUAUAGAAAAGUUCAGGUUUUUAGGCUAUAGCAGAGACAGUGAGAAAGCAUCUGGGCCUUUCUCUUCCUCUUGGUCCAGGGGACCUCAUUCACCAACUAGAGCUUGGUGUACAGGAACGGGGUCACAGUGCUGAGGGGGCUUGAGUCCCACCUUUCAGCUUGAUGGAUGCUCACCUCUUCUCAGCCCCAGCUCGUGCCCUGUUUUUCUAGCCAUAGCCCCCAGAUUACUCACAGCUCCUCAUGCCAUUUCCUGUCCAGAUUGCUAUGUAUGACUCUGACCUCUCUUGUCCAGUGGUCUGGUGCUCACCUCCUCUCACUGCUAGAAUAUUCACCAAGGGUUUGCAUUUGGGAAGUCCCUUACCAGCUCCUGCUUAGAGCUGGUAGGGCCAUACAUGUCCACACUCCCAACUGGUGGCUCUCCCGCUGAAUGGGGCCUCAGCAGGUGCCCAAGCUGCUACAACCUUGGCCACUCUGUUUCUCCACCCCAGCACUGGGCAUGGUAAUUAGCCUUUCCCCAUGUUAAUUUAUUCAGUUUUUUCAAGGGUCAACUGAAUUCCCCACUUCCUGGGUAAGAAGCAUGAUCUCCUUUUAAUUUCACGUCUAAGAUCCUGGCAGCUUCCCCUAGCUGGUUCCUCUGUAGUCCUGCUGGGACUGUCAGCUCAUUUAAAUGUGGGUCUGCAGAAGGCUUUAGGUCUCCCCCAACCCCCUUACCUUUCACAGAGGAACCUUUCAUCAGGAUAAAUGAUUAUUGCUGCCCUGUGGGUCUUGCUCAAUACUGUUCAUACCUGGAGAGAGAAGGUAUUGAAACAUCUCCUUUAUGUGUGACUUUCCCAAAUUUUUAAAAAUUGUUUAUGGUUUAGGCCCCUUAAAUACUGUGUAGCAGGAUGAAGUCUACCAUUACCAGCUGGGUCACCUUGGAUGGGUCUGUCAACAUCUAAGCCUCAGUUCCCUCACCUGUAAAAAUGAGGGUAGUCCCUACCUCAUAAGGGAUAUUGUGAGGAUGGAAAGCGAAAGUGUGAGAAAAUACCUCCCAAGUGCCUGGUACAUAGUGGGUGCUAAAUAAACCACUUUUUGUCUGCAA